AUUCCUCACGAUGACCCGACAGUCUCUGCUUUCUUUUUCCUUUCUUCCAGAAGGAGAUUUAACCAUAGUAGAAAGAAUGGAGAACUAUUAACUGCCUUUCUUCUGUGGGCUGUGAUUUUCAGAGGGGAAUGCUAAGAGAUCUUGUUCUCAGAGGCCAUUCCCAGACCCACAGCAAGAGGGAUUAUGGCUGCAGGCCUCAUGCUCCUUUGUUUUGGAAGAAACUGUUGAGGAGUUAGUAUUUACUGAGCAGCUAAUAUGUUCCCGUCACUAUUGUAACUCAUAAUAAUUAUUGUUAAGUAAUACACGAAAAGUUUUAAAUUUAAAGCAUUCCAAUAUUUUAAAAGUAAAGGGAACAAAAGGCCAAGUGUCCCUUCACUCACUAACCUCUGAUCUUCAGAUUAGCAUGCGUCUUUUUUGAGUUUUUCAGGCAUUUACAUAAAUAGUUAUGCAGAAAUGGAUAGCUUUGCUUCUGUUCUUCAAUUGAAUCUUUAGUAUAGUUGUGCAAGGUGUUUUUUGAUCACUUAGUGUGUCUCCGUUAUCUAGGUUCAUGACAACAAAUCAACUCUUUUUACCUGCUGCAUUGAAUUCCCUCCGAGGGAUGAGCCGUCAUUCCUCUAAGCAGUCUCCUGAUGGGUGGCUGGUUCAGUUGGUUACCAUUUUUAUACUUUAAAAAUAGUGCUGCAGUGUCAUUCUCACAGAGGCUUCUGUCUGCACCCAUGCAAGUACUUUGCUCGACUUGACAUCAGGAAGUGGAACUGCUGGGCCAACUGUGCAAUUCUAAAUUUCACACUUCAUGAUAUUGUAUAAGUAAAUAAAGUUGCAAUGGUUUUGUCCCAUGUCUGAGACCAAAGAGCUUGUGAAUCUUAGAGCCUUUACUUAUUGCUUACCCUCUUUGUGUCCCUAACCCUUAUAUCAUGGGCCUGGCCCCUUGUGGGUGCUUGGUAAAUAUUUGUUGAAUGACUUUAUGAAGGGAAGAAAGAAAAGGUAAGUAAGGCCUGGUCUUAUUUGCAGCUCUGUGAUCACUAGCCUUGGAUUAAAUGUGGUGGGUUCAGCCCCUGACUGACUUCAGGUCCCCCACCAAGCAGUCUUCCUUAAUCCUACCAGGAGUCCACUAGGCCAUGAGUUGACCAUGGUGAUGGCCAAGAGUUGGGGCUUUGAGGAGUCCACAGUGUGGGACACCCACAGCGGUCGACCCCGGUGGAACCAGGGAGCCCAGUGAAGAGUGUCCUGCAUGAAUCAGAGGGGGAUUGUGGUGGGUUGGACUUGGCAGGGGAAGUUUGGGGAAGUCAUAGGAUUCUGAAUAUUGUUAAACAGUACAGUGAGGAUUUUCUGAUCGAAUAACAGAUGUGCAUUUCACAUAGACAUGUUUUUACAGGUGAUUUUCAAUGUUGGGACUCAAAGGUGAAGACACUGAAGGACAGAAUUUUUGGCAGAGGAAAGAUCUUCUUCGGUCACCAUACUUGAGUUAGCUCUAGGGAAGUGGAGGUUUCCAUUUGGAAUUCUAUAGCUUCUUCCAGGUCAUAGUGUCUGCCCCCCACCUUCCAGUAUCUCCUGAUAUGCAGCAUGAAUGAAAAUGGCAAGUUUCCUGGCCUUCCUUCUGCUCAACUUUCGUGUCUGCCUCCUUUUGCUUCAGCUGCUCAUGCCUCACUCAGCUCAGUUUUCUGUGCUUGGACCCUCUGGGCCCAUCCUGGCCAUGGUGGGUGAAGACGCUGAUCUGCCCUGUCACCUGUUCCCGACCAUGAGUGCAGAGACCAUGGAGCUGAAGUGGGUGAGUUCCAGCCUAAGGCAGGUGGUGAACGUGUAUGCAGAUGGAAAGGAAGUGGAAGACAGGCAGAGUGCACCGUAUCGAGGGAGAACUUCGAUUCUGCGGGAUGGCAUCACUGCAGGGAAGGCUGCUCUCCGAAUACACAACGUCACAGCCUCUGACAGUGGAAAGUACUUGUGUUAUUUCCAAGAUGGUGACUUCUAUGAAAAAGCCCUGGUGGAGCUGAAGGUUGCAGCACUGGGUUCUGAUCUUCACGUUGAUGUGAAGGGUUACAAGGAUGGAGGGAUCCAUCUGGAGUGCAGGUCCACUGGCUGGUACCCCCAACCCCAAAUACAGUGGAGCAACAACAAGGGAGAGAACAUCCCGACUGUGGAAGCACCUGUGGUUGCAGACGGAGUGGGCCUGUAUGCAGUAGCAGCAUCUGUGAUCAUGAGAGGCAGCUCUGGGGAGGGUGUAUCCUGUACCAUCAGAAGUUCCCUCCUCGGCCUGGAAAAGACAGCCAGCAUUUCCAUCGCAGACCCCUUCUUCAGGAGCGCCCAGAGGUGGAUCGCCGCCCUGGCAGGGACCCUGCCUGUCUUGCUGCUGCUUCUUGGGGGAGCCGGUUACUUCCUGUGGCAACAGCAGGAGGAAAAAAAGACUCAGUUCAGAAAGAAAAAGAGAGAGCAAGAGUUGAGAGAAAUGGCAUGGAGCACAAUGAAGCAAGAACAAAGCACAAGAGUGAAGCUCCUGGAGGAACUCAGAUGGAGAAGUAUCCAGUAUGCAUCUCGGGGAGAGAGACAUUCAGCCUAUAAUGAAUGGAAAAAGGCCCUCUUCAAGCCUGGUGAGGAAAUGCUUCAGAUGAGGCUCCACUUUGUUAAAUAAAUUGGAUGUAUGGAAAAAUAGACUGCAGAAAAGGGGAACUCAUUUAGCUCAUGAGUGGUCGAAUGAAGGUUGAAAAUUAACCUCUGAGUAUAAAGCAUUAGUGGGCAGAGUGAAUAUGGGGAGGGAAACAAGAAAAACGUAGAAAGGAUCCUUGCUGCUUCCUGAGGCCGCGUCAGGGUAUUGGGUUAGGCAGAGAUGCUGAGGCAACCCUCAUUUCACCCUCCUCUUCCCCUCUGGACACAAGAUACCUGAUACCUGGGGCUUUCUCUCCUGACAUCGAUGAGAGAGUCACAUUUAGGGCAGACUAGGGACACCAGGCUUUGGACUCAGACCUCCUCAGCAUGGCCCAGGCCUUGCAUGCUGAGGCUCUGAAAUCCAGGAAAAAUGGUUGACCUCAUGGACACUUCCUCAAACUCUCUGCAGCGGAUGUGAUUCUGGAUCCAAAAACAGCAAACCCCAUCCUCCUUGUUUCUGAGGACCAGAGGAGUGUGCAGCGUGCCAAGGAGCCCCAGGAUCUGCCAGACAACCCUGAGAGAUUUAAUUGGCAUUAUUGUGUUCUCGGCUGUGAGAGCUUCAUAUCAGGGAGACAUUACUGGGAGGUGGAGGUAGGGGACAGGAAAGAGUGGCAUAUAGGGGUGUGCAGUAAGAAUGUGCAGAGAAAAGGCUGGGUCAAAAUGACACCUGAGAAUGGAUUCUGGACUAUGGGGCUGACUGAUGGGAAUAAGUAUCGGACUCUAACUGAGCCCAGAACCAACCUGAAACUUCCUAAGCCCCCUAAGAAAGUGGGGGUCUUCCUGGACUAUGAGACUGGAGAUAUCUCAUUCUACAAUGCUGUGGAUGGAUCGCAUAUUCAUACUUUCCUGGACGUCUCCUUCUCUGAGGCUCUAUAUCCUGUUUUCAGAAUUUUGACCUUGGAGCCCACGGCCCUGACUAUUUGUCCAGCGUGAAAAGAAGAAGAGAGUUCCUCCAAUUCUGACCGAGUGCUGAUCAUUCCCUAGAGACACCAGUAACCCCGGGCUUAGCUAACGAAAGUGGGGAGCCUCAGGCUGAAGUAACUUUUCUCUGCUUCUCCCUGCCCAGCUCAGAGCUGAGGGCCUCCCCCUCCACAGCAACCAAUCACAACCAUAAAGCUACAAGCACGCACUGAAGCACUUUACUGAUACUCAUUCAAUUAUUCAUAUGACAGUUGUUUGAGUUUGGUACCAUCUUAUUUUCCCCUUAUACAGAUAAGGAAACUGGGGUGCAGAAAAGUGAAUUGACUACAAAGUAGACAUGACUAGUUAACAACACAGCUGGGAUCUAAACAGCAAUAACUAACAUUAAUGGAGAACUUAAAAUGCUCUGAGUGCUGUGUUAUGAGCUUUGGUGGAUGUCACUCCUUUAAUCCUCGCAACACCCUGUCGGGUAGUCUCAUUUAGCAAGUAUGGAAGUUGAGGCAGGGCAACAUUAAGCAACUUACAUAACUCAUGCAGUAAUUUCUGCAGUUGGGAGAUGUUCAGCUUCAGUCCCCGGCCCUAUGGCCGUUCUUUUCCACCCUGUUUCUUCCCCCAUAGGAAGAACCCACCUGUAGCCCUGAGGUUCUUUUCCCAGGAUGGCUCCAGGAUAAGGAUCACUGUAGGUGGUUGUGGAGUUGACACCCCUGUUGACUCCUUCCCAGCUGAUUGUCAGAGCCUUAGACCCAGCACGCCUUGGAUUAGCUCUGCAGAGUGUCUUGGUUGAGAGAAUAACCUCACCGUACCCACAUGACACGUGAUUUGGAAAGAGACUAGAGGCCACACUUGAUAAAUCAUGGGGAACAGAUGUGUUCCACCCAACAAAUGUGAUAAGUGAUCAUGCAGCCAGAGCCAGCCUUCCUUCAAUCAAGGUUUCCAGGCAGAGCAAAUACCCUAGAGAUUCUCUGUGAUAUAGGAAAUUUGGAUGAAGGGAGCUAGAAGAAAUACAGGGAUUUUUUUUUUUUUUUAAGAUGGAGUCUUACUCUGUUGCUAGGCUGGAGUGCAGUGGUGCGAUCUCAGCUCCCUGCAACCUCCACCUCCUGGGUUCAAACAAUUCUCCUGCCUCAGCCUCCCGAGUACUGGGAAUAUAGGUGCACGCCACCACACCCAACAAAUUUUUGUACUUUUAGUACAGAUGAGGGUUCACUAUGUUGGCCAGGAUGGUCUCGAUCUCUUGACCUCAUGAUCCACCCACCUCGGUCUCCCAAAGUGCUGGGAUUACAGGCUUGAGCCACCGGGUGACCGGCUUACAGGGAUAUUUUUAAUCCCGUUAUGGACUCUGUCUCCAGGAGAGGGGUCUAUCCACCCCUGCUCAUUGGUGGAUGUUAAACCAAUAUUCCUUUCAACUGCUGCCUGCUAGGGAAAAACUACUCCUCAUUAUCAUCAUUAUUAUUGCUCUCCACUGUAUCCCCUCUACCUGGCAUGUGCUUGUCAAGUUCUAGUUGUUCAAUAAAUUUGUUAAUAAUGCUGA